AGAUUUUCCAGCGGAUCCCCCGGUGGCCUCAUGUCGCGCAGUGGAACCGAUCCUCAGCAACGCCAGCAGGCGUCAGAGGCGGACGCCGCAGCAGCAACCUUCCGGGCAAACGACCAUCAGCAUAUCCGCUACAACCCGCUGCAGGAUGAGUGGGUGCUGGUGUCAGCUCACCGCAUGAAGCGGCCCUGGCAGGGUCAAGUGGAGCCCCAGCUUCUGAAGACAGUGCCCCGCCAUGACCCUCUCAACCCUCUGUGUCCUGGGGCCAUCCGAGCCAACGGAGAGGUGAAUCCCCAGUACGAUAGCACCUUCCUGUUUGACAACGACUUCCCAGCUCUGCAGCCUGAUGCCCCCAGUCCAGGACCCAGUGAUCAUCCCCUUUUCCAAGCAAAGUCUGCUCGAGGAGUCUGUAAGGUCAUGUGCUUCCACCCCUGGUCGGAUGUAACGCUGCCACUCAUGUCGGUCCCUGAGAUCCGGGCUGUUGUUGAUGCAUGGGCCUCAGUCACAGAGGAGCUGGGUGCCCAGUACCCUUGGGUGCAGAUCUUUGAAAACAAAGGUGCCAUGAUGGGCUGUUCUAACCCCCACCCCCACUGCCAGGUAUGGGCCAGCAGUUUCCUGCCAGAUAUUGCCCAGCGUGAGGAGCGAUCUCAGCAGGCCUAUAAGAGUCAGCAUGGAGAGCCCCUGCUAAUGGAGUACAGCCGCCAGGAGCUACUCAGGAAGGAACGUCUGGUCCUAACCAGUGAGCACUGGUUAGUACUGGUCCCCUUCUGGGCAACAUGGCCCUACCAGACACUGCUGCUGCCCCGUCGGCAUGUGCGGCGGCUACCUGAGCUGACCCCUGCUGAGCGUGAUGAUCUAGCCUCCAUCAUGAAGAAGCUCUUGACCAAGUAUGACAACCUCUUUGAGACGUCCUUUCCCUACUCCAUGGGCUGGCAUGGGGCUCCCACAGGAUCAGAGGCUGGGGCCAACUGGAACCAUUGGCAGCUGCACGCUCAUUACUACCCUCCGCUCCUGCGCUCUGCCACUGUCCGGAAAUUCAUGGUUGGCUACGAAAUGCUUGCUCAGGCUCAGAGGGACCUCACCCCUGAGCAGGCUGCAGAGAGACUAAGGGCACUUCCUGAGGUUCAUUACCACCUGGGGCAGAAGGACAGGGAGACAGCAACCAUCGCCUGACCACGCCGACCACAGGGCCUUGAAUCCUUUUUUGUUUUCAACAGUCUUGCUGAAUUAAGCAGAAAGGGCCUUGAAUCCUGGCCUGGAAUUUGGGCAGAUAUAGCAUUAAUAAAACUGUGCAUCUCAAACUUUUAUCACAUACUCUAAUAUCAGAGGAGUGUGAACCUUCAGAGAUCUAGGGUUAAAAGCUAAAGGCAUAGCUCCAGCUACAACUUUUCUUUGUCUACAGAUGUGUAAAAUCUUGAUGCAAAAAUCUACCCCAAAUUUCUGAACAAAAUUAAUAUUCAGUAUUAUAUCUAGCCUAUAGAUUCUCUUACUCUUGGUGUAAUGACAGCAUUCCCAGUUUAGGAAACUGUUUUAAAAUCUUGUGUCUUGGUUGUGGCUGAGGCUUUGGGAAGGCCAGAGCCCCCUUUGCCACCACCCCUAGGGUGUCAGCUCCAAGCCUGGGCCUGAGGGUUUGAUGGGGAGCGGGUGAGCUGGAUCCUGAUCCCAGUGGUCAGUGGCCAGAUCCUGGGCUGCUGGCCAGAACCCUGGCUUUGUGAGUGGCUGCAGCUUGGCUCUGCUCCAGCCCACAGGGGCUAAAGGG